CAUAUUUAAGCCCCUGUCAAAUUCGAGUGCUGACUUUACCAAAACUAGAUUGGAACAUAAACUAUUGAUGAACAUGUAAAAAUUGUUCAUAGACGAGUAUUCAGUUACUGUACCCCCUCAACAGGGAAAGCAGUUUGAGUAAACCAUUGCAUGGUUGUUUUUUCCUCUUACUGUUGCUCUUUGAGGCAAUUUUGAGAGAGGUACUAUUAUUUUCUGAUGUUGUAUAGAGAUAGGUGACCUGCUGUUGAGCGAGCAUUUUAAAAAACUCAUUUUAUGAGGUCUCCAUGCAUAAUUGAAAUAACCCAAUGUUGCUGUCAUUUCCACCAAAAUUUAUGAGAUUGUCACUCAGGAAACUUAAGAAUACUAAAUUUGCUUUUGAAAAAGCAAAUAUAUUUACAUGGAUGUGCAUUGCACAACCAAAAACUUACCUUUUUAUUAUCUGAAAAUUCUAAAUAAAUCCUUUGGCAUACUUUUAGUUAUAUUCUUAUCUAAGGCUGCUUCAAAACCUAUUUUUAUCAUAAUUCUAUCAUAUAAAAUGUGAAAGAUAACUGUCCAGCAUGAGGGUUAUUGCUUUUGAUUGGAAGUGAAUCUCAGUUGUCCUAUGUAUGUUGGAGAAAUAUUUCAUUAAUAAUUUAUUGAAAACAUUUUCUUUGUCAUCUUUCUGAAUGAAUGAGUAUGAAUGGCGCUUCCCUGUCUUUAAAGGAGUAUAUUACUGACAUACAAAACUCAAAUGUUAAAUUUGUCUGAAAAAUAUAUUUCUACAUGAUCUGAUAAAGUUCAGAUAAGGGGCAUUCUGUUCCUAAGAAUGUCCUAAAAAUGGAAAGCUGAUAAAAGAUUAUGCUUAGAAUUAUACAGGUAAAAGACCUACAACAGUUGUUCUCUUGUUUUGAUCCCAUAGGUUAUUUGUUAUUACUCUUCUUUAACAGAGUGAUUUUCUAUUCUUAACCUUCUUAAGAGCCAAUACAGAGUAGAAAGAAAUAUUUUCAGAAAGCCUUUUUAAUAGUAACUUAAUGUAAAAAUUGUUUAUCCUUUGGUUGAGGUUUCCCAUUUCCAUUUUUAAGCUUAUCUGAACUGUGAACAUGAAAAACGUAAUGAUUCAUUGGUCAAGAAGCUACCAUUUGAGGGCUCUAAAGUUUCUUUUAGAUUUCCUUUUUUAUAUCAGUACAAUUAAAAUUUGAUUUAUCAAGUAGCAGCAGCUUCUUGAUAUUGUUACAUACAUUAGCUUGUUCAUAAAAUGUUAGAGUUAAAACUCAUUAAAAAUGCUAUCGUUAAACAUAAACUAAUUAAAAUUCAGUAUACGAGAUUCUCCCUUCAAAAACAUCUUAUUUUUAUUUUAUUUAGUACUUGCUUCAGUGUUUUCUAGGAAUAUCUAGUAAAGGCCUUUACUGUUUUCCACAUGGCCUAAUUUUAUAUUGGACUACAAUUUUUGAGAAGGAAUGCCAAAUACAAAAUUUUGAAUCAAUAAAUUACAAUUAUAAUUUUUAUACUUAUUUUCAAAGUUAAUUUACUUUAGAUGGCAGUAAAAUCACUGAACUUCUGAUUGAAAGAAAAUUUUUUAGUUUGAAAUUUCCUUCUGGAAAGGGGUUUGCAGUCCCUUUGGAAAGGAGUAAGCAAUCCUGGAAGUAAUUGAGUAUUUAAUCCUCCUAUAUUUUUUCUGAAGAUUUUUGUGUCAGUAUACUUUCUUUAUGCUGGCUAGAAAGAUCAGUUCUCAAGAGUUGCAGGAUAAAAUCAAAUUAACUUUCAUGUUUCAGAACUAAAACAUAUCCUUGCAUUUAUGGGAAGGAUAGGUAAAAAUGGAGAUGGUGGCUGAUAAAAUAAAAAUCUUUGAAACUAUGUUUUUACAAGCCCAAAGCCUUUUGGAGUUGAAAGUAUUAAAAAAAAGUAUGAUAUGCUAUCUUCAGGUUAUGUAUAUGAUCACAGAUAAUAGCUCUGAUGGUCACAGAGCUUGCUGAUGGCUUCCAAAGGAUGGCUCCUGCCUUUUACCUUGUUACCACAGCUCCUCAUAGGGCACUUUGAGUGGCAGUUCUGGAAUCUGAAAAAGAAAGGAUAGUGUAAGAAUGGUGGUAAAAUAAAAAGAACUGUCUUUAUAGUUCCUGCUUUAUAGGCUCAAUAAGGAUUUUUAAUACAUCCUUGCAAAAUUGUUUUUGUAGUUUUUGUUACAAAUCUGUUACUUUGCAAUUCCUAAGGAGUAGAUUUGGUGCUGUUAGUAUGGGUAUUUGCAAGACAUCCCUCAAGGAUUCUUAUGUUUUGUGCAUUAACUACUGUCUUCAUUACUUACACAUCUAAAAACUCCCCCUUCCUUAGGCAUAUGUCAUUUUUAUUCAACAUAAUUUUGCAUAUAUUGCUUUCUUUGGCUGGAACAAUUAUAUACAUGAUGAAAAUCAGAUUUUCUUCUAUAAAUCUAUUUGUAAUUUUUACAGUAACUUUAUUUCUAGUACUGUAUUUGUCAUAAUGAUUUUGCUCUCGGGGGUCUAUAUAGAAGAAAACUUGAUUCUUUUUGGAAUAGUACUGCUCAAGAAAUGUGGAAGAAGUGAUAUAUGGCACUAUACCCAUGAAUCACUAAAGAAACAGUGGUUUUAUUUUGAACAUUUUUGAAGAAAUUCAAAGAUUUGGGACUAAAGUUACCAAGUUAAUUUGGUAUUUAUUUUGUCCUUUGUAUUCUUAUUUUUUAGGUUAAAGAAUAGGAAGAAACCACAAUAAAAGCUGGAAUUAUAAAGUCAUAGAGUGGAAAGGGAUUUAGAGAUUAUCUAGUCCAACCUUUUCAUUCUGUAGAUUAUGCUAAAUUCUUGAAAAGUCAUGUAAAGUCCAGGUUAUAGAAAUUUUAUUUACAAUCUGGAAGAAACUGAUAGCUAGAAAAAGAAUGCUGCAUACUUAUUCAUAUUAUUAAUGCCUUUACUAUAAAUUUAAGCUUAUUUAAGCUCAAAAUUUUAUUAACCACUCUGCUCUGAAUUUAUUUUAGUUAAGGAUUAGAAGCAUCAAACAUUUUGCUGGAAAACAAAAUGACAUUUGGGGAAACAUUCUUUCCCCUUUUGCUGUUACUGAUAGCUUAUUAAUUCUGGCUGUAAUUUUUUUGUCUUUAUAUACAUUAAUCAAAAAGACAAAGAUGUUGUAUAAAAUAGUCAUGAAAAAGAUUGAGUAAAUAGUUUAUAGCUUUGUAGUAACUUCUGGGAUAGGACACUAAUAUAGCUGUCAGGAAACCUUGAUUUUAGUUUCCUAUGUACCUUCAGUUCGUUUUUCUUAAACAUUGGUAUAAAAAUAUGGAUGUAAAAGGAAGAAGGUAUUUUGUAGGGUAGUUGUAAGUUCCUGAAUGUGUGGAAUGAUUUAUGUGCAAACAUUGUCUUGCCUAAUGGAAAUAGUCAUAAUUGCCUAGUUUUCAUUAGUCUGAAAAAUGUCUUAAAGAAGUAUUGGGCUCAUCUUAAAUCAAGAGCAACAGAAGUCUCUUCAUCAGCUGCUGUUAGAACAUGAGUCUGCGCAGCCAUAGAGUAGGGAUCUGCAGACCCUGCAAGAACAGUUCCUGUCACUGGCCACUGUCAGUGGUCAUUAAUAAUUAUAACAAUGUAAGAAAACAAGAUAAUAUAGAAGAGUCAAACUUUGAACUUUAAACAAAACAUGUUUGCUACAUUUUAACAGUCAUAAAUAGGGCAAUGGGGGGGCGGGGCAUAAGUUUUAGAAUAUGUUUUAUGUCAUUUAAGAAUCUGACUUGCAAGUACCUGAAUGGGAGAGAAGUGCUGAUUAUUACAAAGUAGUGGAGCAAGGAGAGUUGAGGAGUAGUUGGUUUUAAGGGGUUUGUAAAGCUGUGUUGAUGUUUUGGGUAAUAAAACUAGAUUCGGGGUAGAAAUGCUUUUUCUACCCACGUAUUCAUAAAUUUAUGUAAGAAGAAAUGCUAGUAAGUGUUAAUAACCUGAGAAGCUCUAGCUUUUUCCUUCCUUUUUUUGGGGUAAUACCUUCAUAUGUUAAUUUCAGAUUUUUUCAUGAGCAAAGAUGUUCGUGAAACUUAGCCAUAAACCAUAUUCUCUGAAUAUCAAGUGUCAUCCCUAACAUUCAGGCUUAAUAACUUAAUGUUUAUGUGACUUACGUGCUAGCAAUGUGGAAGAAAUUUUUUAUCUAGUAAUGUUUGGUGUGUAUUAUCUUAACAUUAGUGCUGAAUUUUAGAAAGCACUUCUAUUUUGGUGACUUUUGGAACACAUGGGUAGAGCAUUGUCAAGUGGCUUGGUUAGUUUCCAUUACCCUUAUACAAGUGUUGUCAUUCUGUACAAUUUGGUGCCUCUUCCCUGACAGUGUGAUAGUUUCAGGAGUUGAAGGGAAAGCAUUGCAUGUUAAAAGCUAAAGUGGACAGAAGUUAUCUUUAUUUCCCUCUUCUGUACUACUUUACACCUACAGUCACUUAUUUUUUUUUUUUGCAACAUUCAUUGAAAACUCCACAUUAUUUCAAACAUUAUGUUCUUUUUUGACUUAUUCAUGUUGUCAAUGCCUUUAUGAUAAUUUUAAGCUUAUUUUUAAAUAUUUCAAGAUUUAUUACAUUCAAAACUCUUAUAAAGCAUUUUGUUCAUGGUAUAAUAGUAUUUUGAUCUGAGUAGUAAUAGAUUUAUUUGUUUAAAUAUAGAUAAAAAUUGGUCAGUGUGUGUUCUCCAAAAAAAAAUCUUGAUAAUGGGGAAAAUCAGAGAUUAGACAGGAAAAGAAGAUAUUGUGGCUAAGAUUUGACUGCACUUACGCUUUCAUCUCUCUUGCCUUUUUAUUCUCUGAGAAGGUCCCUAAAAUUGUAGUUAAUGCUGCUUUAUUAUUAUGUUCAGUGACUUAACUUCAAUGUGUAUCUAAUAUCACUGAACAGUAACUAGGGUCCGAACAUUUGCUCAUUAACUCCUGAAAGUAGUCUGUUGUGAUACGUCACCAAACAAAGGUUUCAAAUGUAGAAGCAUGAAAGGUUCUUUAAUUAUUUGAUGUGAAUUAGUUAAAAGUUCCUUGAAAUUUUAUUUUGGAUGAUCUUAACUCACUUUUUUCUAAUGAAAUUUUUGCUUUCAACUGGUAGUAACUGGUCCUGGGCAUUCAGAUUUUUAUAUUUAUGUAUGUAUGCAAGAUACACUAUUCUCUUUUGAGAAAAUGUUGUCUUAGCUAAUUUCUGGGAUUUGUGAAAGGAAAUGUAAUAUGUUAAUAGCUAUUAUUGGCACUCUAUGUUACAAUAUUAAGGAUCUAAAUAGAUUCCCACUUAGCCACGAUGCUUUUCUUAAGCAUAAUUCAUCUCUACGUAAAUAUCCCAUAUGAAAGAAAAUUUAGAGCCCUCCAUUUAAAAAAGCUUUCUUGCUCUGCAUAAAACUUGAAAAUAAUUAAUUUCAAAGUUAUAUUGAUAUUAAAACAUAGAUUCAGUCUUGUCUUAAAAGUGUAUUACAAUUUAUUUCUUGCCAUUUUUGUGUAAAAUUUACAGAAAGAGUGUUACACCGUGCGCUCCAAAGUACCACAAAGCCUGCUCCACACCUGGAUGGGGUGCAUGUAGUCUUUGGACUGGUUAUUUCUGGUUUUGAAGUAAUCGAACAAAUUGAAAAUCUGAAGACCGAUGCUGCAAGCAGACCAUAUGCAGAUGUGCGAGUUAUUGACUGUGGAGUACUUGCCACAAAAUCAAUAAAAGAUGUUUUUGAGAAAAAAAGGAAGAAACCAACUCAUUCAGAAGGCUCGGAUUCCUCUUCCAAUUCCUCCUCUUCUUCAGAAUCAUCUUCAGAAAGUGAACUUGAACAUGAGAGAAGCAGAAGGAGGAAACAUAAGAGGAGGCCAAAAGUUAAACGUUCUAAAAAGAGGCGAAAGGAAGCAAGCAGUUCAGAAGAGCCAAGGAAUAAACAUGCAAUGAACCCAAAAGGUCACUCUGAGAGGAGUGAUACCAAUGAAAAAAGGUCAGUUGAUUCCAGUGCUAAAAGGGAAAAACCUGUGGUCCGCCCAGAAGAGAUUCCUCCAGUGCCUGAGAACCGAUUUUUACUGAGAAGAGAUAUGCCUGUUGUUACUGCAGAACCUGAACCGAAGAUUCCUGAUGUUGCACCCAUUGUAAGUGAUCAGAAACCAUCUGUAUCAAAGUCUGGACGGAAGAUUAAAGGAAGGGGCACAAUUCGCUAUCACACACCUCCAAGAUCAAGAUCCUGUUCUGAGUCAGAUGAUGAUGACAGCAGUGAAACUCCUCCUCACUGGAAAGAGGAAAUGCAGAGAUUAAGAGCAUAUAGACCACCUAGUGGAGAAAAAUGGAGUAAAGGAGAUAAGUUAAGUGACCCCUGUUCAAGCCGAUGGGAUGAAAGAAGCUUGUCUCAGAGAUCCAGAUCAUGGUCCUAUAAUGGAUAUUAUUCAGACCUUAGUACAGCAAGACACUCUGGCCACCAUAAAAAACGCAGAAAAGAAAAAAAGGUUAAGCAUAAAAAGAAAGGGAAAAAGCAGAAACACUGCAGAAGACACAAACAAACAAAGAAGAGAAGGAUUCUUAUACCGUCUGACAUAGAAUCCUCAAAAUCUUCCACUCGAAGAAUGAAAUCCUCUUGUGAUAGAGAAAGGAGUUCUCGUUCUUCCUCAUUGUCAUCUCAUCACUCAUCAAAGAGAGACUGGUCUAAAUCUGAUAAGGAUGUCCAGAGCUCUUUAACCCAUUCCAGCAGAGACUCAUACAGAUCAAAAUCUCACUCACAGUCUUAUUCUAGAGGAAGCUCAAGAUCAAGGACUGCGUCAAAGUCCUCAUCACAUUCUCGAAGUAGAUCAAAGUCCAGAUCUAGUUCCAAGUCUGGGCACCGAAAGAGAGCAUCAAAAUCACCAAGAAAAACAGCUUCUCAGUUAAGUGAAAAUAAACCAGUUAAAACAGAACCUUUAAGAGCAACCAUGGCACAAAAUGAAAAUGUAGUAGUACAACCAGUUGUAGCAGAAAAUAUUCCUGUAAUACCACUGAGUGACAGUCCCCCCCCUUCAAGAUGGAAGCCUGGACAGAAACCUUGGAAGCCCUCUUAUGAGCGAAUUCAGGAAAUGAAAGCUAAAACAACCCAUUUGCUACCCAUCCAAAGCACUUACAGUUUAGCAAAUAUUAAAGAGACUGGUAGCUCAUCAUCCUACCAUAAAAGAGAAAAAAAUUCGGAAAGUGAUCAGAGCACUUAUUCAAAAUACAGUGAUAGAAGUUCAGAAAGCUCACCAAGGUCAAGGAGCAGAUCUUCUAGGAGUAGAUCUUAUUCCAGAUCAUAUACAAGAUCACGUAGUCUAGCUAGUUCACAUUCAAGGUCUAGGUCUCCAUCAUCUAGAUCUCAUUCACGAAAUAAAUACAGUGAUCAUUCACAGUGUAGUAGAUCAUCUUCAUAUACUUCUAUUAGCAGUGAUGAUGGAAGGCGAGCUAAGAGGAGACUUAGAUCCAGUGGGAAAAAAAAUAGCGUUUCACAUAAAAAGCAUAGCAGCAGCUCUGAAAAGACACUUCACAGUAAAUAUGUCAAAGGUAGAGACAGGUCUUCAUGUGUGAGAAAGUAUAGCGAGAGCAGAUCAUCUUUAGAUUAUUCUUCAGACAGUGAGCAGUCAAGUGUUCAGGCCACACAGUCAGCCCAGGAAAAAGAGAAGCAGGGCCAAAUGGAAAGAACACAUAAUAAACAAGAAAAAAACAGAGGUGAAGAAAAAUCCAAGUCUGAACGGGAAUGCCCUCAUUCAAAAAAAAGAACUUUGAAAGAGAAUCUUUCUGAUCACCUUAGAAAUGGCAGUAAGCCCAAAAGGAAGAAUUAUGCUGGUAGUAAAUGGGACUCUGAGUCAAAUUCAGAACGAGAUGUCACUAAAAACAGUAAAAAUGACUCCCAUCCAUCCUCUGACAAGGAAGAAGGUGAGGCCACAUCCGAUUCUGAAUCAGAGGUUAGUGAAAUUCACAUCAAAGUCAAACCCACAACCAAGUCGUCCACAAAUACUUCACUGCCUGAUGAUAAUGGUGCUUGGAAAUCAAGCAAACAGCGCACAUCAACUUCUGACUCUGAGGGGUCCUGUUCCAAUUCGGAAAACAAUAGGGGAAAGCCACAAAAGCACAAACAUGGGUCAAAGGAAAAUCUUAAAAGAGAACACACCAAAAAAGUGAAAGAGAAAUUGAAAGGGAAAAAAGACAAAAAGCAUAAGGCUCCAAAACGAAAGCAAGCAUUUCACUGGCAGCCUCCACUAGAAUUUGGUGAAGAGGAGGAGGAGGAGAUUGAUGACAAGCAAGUUACUCAGGAAUCAAAAGAGAAAAAAGUUUCUGAAAACAAUGAAACCAUAAAAGAUAAUAUUCUAAAAACUGAGAAAUCCAGUGAAGAGGACCUUUCAGGUAAACAUGAUACAGUGACUGUUUCAUCAGAUCUUGAUCAGUUUACUAAAGAUGAUAGUAAACUCAGUAUUUCUCCCACAGCUUUAAAUACUGAGGAAAAUGUGGCCUGUUUACAAAACAUUCAGCACGUUGAAGAAAGUGUUCCCAAUGGAGUGGAAGAUGUGCUUCAAACAGAUGACAACAUGGAGAUCUGCACUCCUGAUAGGAGUUCCCCAGCAAAAGUAGAGGAGACUUCCCCUCUAGGAAAUGCACGGCUUGAUACCCCAGAUAUAAACAUUGUUUUGAAGCAGGAUAUGGCAACGGAACAUCCUCAAGCAGAGGUAGUAAAACAGGAAAGCAGCAUGUCCGAAAGUAAAGUGUUGGGUGAAGUGGGGAAACAGGACAGCAGCUCUGCUAGCUUGGCUAGUGCUGGAGAAAGUACCGGGAAGAAGGAGGUGGCUGAGAAGAGCCAGAUCAACCUCAUUGAUAAGAAAUGGAAGCCCCUGCAAGGUGUGGGGAACCUGGCAGCACCUAAUGCUGCCACAUCCAGUGCUGUGGAAGUUAAGGUGUUGACCACUGUGCCUGAAAUGAAACCACAAGGCUUGAGAAUAGAAAUUAAAAGCAAAAAUAAAGUUCGGCCUGGGUCUCUCUUUGAUGAAGUAAGAAAGACAGCACGCUUAAACCGUAGACCAAGAAAUCAGGAGAGUUCAAGUGAUGAGCAGACGCCUAGUCGGGAUGAUGAUAGCCAGUCCAGGAGUCCAAGUAGAUCUCGAAGUAAAUCUGAAACCAAAUCAAGACACAGAACAAGGUCUGUCUCCUAUAGUCACUCAAGAAGUCGAUCGAGAAGUUCCACAUCAUCUUAUCGAUCAAGAAGCUACUCUAGAAGUCGGAGCAGAGGAUGGUACAGCAGAGGCCGAACCAGAAGCCGGAGCAGUUCCUACCGGAGUUACAAAAGUCACAGGACGUCCAGCAGGAGCAGAUCCAGGAGCAGCUCAUAUGAUCCCCACAGUCGAUCCAGCAGGUCCUACACCUACGAUAGCUACUAUAGCAGGAGUCGGAGUCGAAGUAGAAGCCAGAGAAGUGACAGUUACCACCGAGGCAGAAGUUAUAAUCGGCGGUCCAGGAGUUGUAGAUCUUAUGGCUCUGACAGUGAAAGUGACCGAAGUUACUCUCAUCACCGGAGCCCCAGUGAGAGCAGCAGAUACAGUUGAAAACGUCCGGAUACAAAUUAUAUCUUAUUUGUAAAUAUCUGGCAACUUAGCUUAAGAAAUGUAAUGACAGUCUGUUGUUCUAUUUCAAUAUCAGAGGUGAAUUUCAAAAAUAGACACUUCUUAAUUGUUACUGGUUCAUUUACAUGUGGGGAGAAGAAUUUAAAAUACAGAUAUGUCUCCUAAAAAUAUUUUUAUGCCACAUUUUACAGUAGCCAACUAUGGAAAUGAAUUUCAUUUUCUUGAAUCAAGAAAUCGUGAAAUUUAUCUAUGUAUAAUUUGCAAUAUUAUUUUAAGUCUAUUUCACUCUAUCUUACGUAUCCCUUAGAAUACAGAUUCUUUUUGCCUGUUUUUCCAGUUUUAGCAUAUAUGCUGCCAAGCAUAGAACUGUGAAGGAGAACUGUUAAAGGCGGCCAAAUAUUUAUAUACUGAUUACAUAGAGUCUUGUACAUAUGUGCUCUAAAAACAAACCACCCAGAAUUGAUACUGUUGGUAACCAGGAGUAUAAGGCAGUGGCUCUGGGGUUCUUAAUUCAUUCCUAACUUCUUUGAUACUUCACAGGAUUAGGAAAGUGGUCAUCAUACAUCCCACACAGUCUGUAUUACUUCAGGCUUGUGGGCAAGGUUAGGAAGAAUCAAUCAGCCUUAACUAUAAAUACCUGCACUGUCUCUGAGGACUUACUAUUUUAUGUUCUUUUUAAUCAAUACCGAUCAGAAGUUUAGGUUAUAAAAACAAUUCUACUUCAUGCUUUGGUGCUUGGUAAUUUUUGGUGCGUCUUUAAGCAUUACUCUUAUAUAUCAUAUAUUAAAAUACCAUAAAAAUGAAAUUCAGACAAAAUCACUGGCACCAAAAAUGGUUUAUUCUGAGCUGUCUUCACUUUGACUAUUUGGGGGGCUUCUCUCAAGUACAGAUGUGGGUUGGGGUCCCCUGGAGCAGGCAGGAUUGGCAGUAAGAGAUAUUGGCCACUCAAGUCUACUGUGUGUGUGUGCCUCUGGAAGAGUGAAGAAUGGACUUCAAAAGUAACAUCAAAAAUCUAACUGCCACCAUCCUGGAGACAUUUUGCAGGGCUUUCCUUUCAAGUCUUUCAAGUACAGGAUAUUACCACAACAGCAGCUGAACUGUUGUAACCAGCAUGUUUUUCCUAUUUCCACUGUGACCUGCAGCUGACUCAAAGCCUUGCGUGACCUGACCCAGGUGCAAGAGACAGGGGAAGAGGGAUAGAGGGUAUAGCAUAAAUUACAUAUUUUCAUGGCUUUGGGUGGUUCCUCCAAAAAUAAUUGGACCUGUAAAAACUAGUGUGUGUGUGUGUGUGUGUGUGUGUGUGUGUGUGGUUUUUUUUUUUAAUCUUUACUUUGAAUUUGUUCCCCAAGUGUACUUAAUCACCUUAGUGCCAGUUUAAUCCAGUUAUGCAGAAGAAAUUCAUAUUGGUUGCCUGAUGUAGAGCUCAGCACCACCCUACCACAGGCCUUGUCUGGUGUAUUUGGGAAGUGGAAAAGAGCCCUCAGUUGGAGGGAGCUGACAACCCUUGGUGGAGGGAGGGUGCCCUUGAAUGUAUUAAAACUAUCACCCAAAGAAGGUAUGAAAACAGGGUAAGGUGGUCAGUUGUUUGCCAGGUCAAUAGACAGAAAGUACAUUAGAAAACAGGACUUAGGCCAAACAAACAAUACUGGAUACUGAAUACAAAACAGUAUGAUUUAUAUUAAAGGUUUCCAAAGGUUGCCUGCAAAGGAGAAUAUUACUACUAGUCAGCAGGAAAAAAAUGCAUUCAGAACCCAAGCAGAAACUGCCAAAUGUAAUUAGGUUAAGAAAAGUUACCCUUGGGCAGUGUAUUAGUUUUCUAUUGCUGUGUGACAAAUUACCCCAAAUUUAGCAGUUUAAAAAACAAUACCCAUAGCAGUUCUGUAGCUCAUGAGUCUGGCACAGUGUGGCUGGAUUCUCUGCUCAGGGUCUUAAAGGCUGAAAUAAGGGUUGGCAGGACAACAUUCCUUCAUGGAGGCUCUGGGGAAGAAUCUGCUUCUAAGUUCAUUCAGGUUGUUGGCGGAAUUCAGUUCUUUGCUGGCUCUCAGCUGGAGGCCCCUCUCUCACCUCAAGGCUGCCUGCAUUCCUUCUUAUGUGGUCCCCUCCAGCUUCAAACCAGCCUUCCUGCUCUUUCUCAUGCUUCAUAUCUCUCUCCCGUCCUCCUGUUUUAGGGGCAUAUGAUUAGCUCAAGCCCACAGAUAUAUUUUAAGGUUGAUUGUGCGAUAGAACAUAAUUGCAGGAGUACUGUCUCAUCUCAUCAUAUUCACGGGUUCUGGAGAUUAGCUCAUUGAAAGUGGGAGGGGCAUUUUCAAAUUCUGCCUACCACAGGCAAUAACUGCCCAUCUCAGCUGUAGGUGGAAUUUUUACCCAGAAAAGAUAGGCCCUAGAAGCCUCAUUUCUUUUCUCCAUGGAAAAGGACAGCCCUCUGCUGCAGCGUUCAACUUGUGUGUUUACUGACAGAGUGAACUACAGAAAUAGCUUUUCUUCCUAAAGGGGAUUGUUCUACAUUUUGAAGUUAUUUUUUAAUAAAAUUGAAUUAUGUUGUGUAUUGUGCUUCUUAAUAGGAAAUGCAUUAUUGGACUGUUUUUGUAACAUCCUGUUUAUUGCAAAUAGCUAGUAUCGUUCAAAAACUGUAUAAAAUACUUUUGUACAUAUUAGCAAUGUCUAAUUUGUAUACACUUCAGUUAAAUUUCCCUAAAACUUGAAAGGGGACCUUGUAGAAAUUAAAAUAUAUACUUAGUCUAA